AUCCAGUCUAGGAUCCUCACACCAGCUACUUGCAAGGGAGAAGGAAAAGGCCAGUAAGGCCUGGGCCAGGAGAGUCCCGACAGGAGUGUCAGGUUUCAAUCUCAGCACCAGCCACUCAGAGCAGGGCACGAUGUUGGGGGCCCGCCUCAGGCUCUGGGUCUGUGCCUUGUGCAGCGUCUGCAGCAUGAGCGUCCUCAGAGCCUAUCCCAAUGCCUCCCCACUGCUCGGCUCCAGCUGGGGUGGCCUGAUCCACCUGUACACAGCCACAGCCAGGAACAGCUACCACCUGCAGAUCCACAAGAAUGGCCAUGUGGAUGGCGCACCCCAUCAGACCAUCUACAGUGCCCUGAUGAUCAGAUCAGAGGAUGCUGGCUUUGUGGUGAUUACAGGUGUGAUGAGCAGAAGAUACCUCUGCAUGGAUUUCAGAGGCAACAUUUUUGGAUCACACUAUUUCGACCCGGAGAACUGCAGGUUCCAACACCAGACGCUGGAAAACGGGUACGACGUCUACCACUCUCCUCAGUAUCACUUCCUGGUCAGUCUGGGCCGGGCGAAGAGAGCCUUCCUGCCAGGCAUGAACCCACCCCCGUACUCCCAGUUCCUGUCCCGGAGGAACGAGAUCCCCCUAAUUCACUUCAACACCCCCAUACCACGGCGGCACACCCGGAGCGCCGAGGACGACUCGGAGCGGGACCCCCUGAACGUGCUGAAGCCCCGGGCCCGGAUGACCCCGGCCCCGGCCUCCUGUUCACAGGAGCUCCCGAGCGCCGAGGACAACAGCCCGAUGGCCAGUGACCCAUUAGGGGUGGUCAGGGGCGGUCGAGUGAACACGCACGCUGGGGGAACGGGCCCGGAAGGCUGCCGCCCCUUCGCCAAGUUCAUCUAGGGUCGCUGGAAGGGCACCCUCUUUAACCCAUCCCUCAGCAAACGCAGCUCUUCCCAAGGACCAGGUCCCUUGACGUUCCGAGGAUGGGAAAGGUGACAGGGGCAUGUAUGGAAUUUGCUGCUUCUCUGGGGUCCCUUCCACAGGAGGUCCUGUGAGAACCAACCUUUGAGGCCCAAGUCAUGGGGUUUCACCGCCUUCCUCACUCCAUAUAGAACACCUUUCCCAAUAGGAAACCCCAACAGGUAAACUAGAAAUUUCCCCUUCAUGAAGGUAGAGAGAAGGGGUCUCUCCCAACAUAUUUCUCUUCCUUGUGCCUCUCCUCUUUAUCACUUUUAAGCAUAAAAAAAAAAAAAAAAAAAAAAAAAAAAAAAAGCAGUGGGUUCCUGAGCUCAAGACUUUGAAGGUGUAGGGAAGAGGAAAUCGGAGAUCCCAGAAGCUUCUCCACUGCCCUAUGCAUUUAUGUUAGAUGCCCCGAUCCCACUGGCAUUUGAGUGUGCAAACCUUGACAUUAACAGCUGAAUGGGGCAAGUUGAUGAAAACACUACUUUCAAGCCUUCGUUCUUCCUUGAGCAUCUCUGGGGAAGAGCUGUCAAAAGACUGGUGGUAGGCUGGUGAAAACUUGACAGCUAGACUUGAUGCUUGCUGAAAUGAGGCAGGAAUCAUAAUAGAAAACUCAGCCUCCCUACAGGGUGAGCACCUUCUGUCUCGCUGUCUCCCUCUGUGCAGCCACAGCCAGAGGGCCCAGAAUGGCCCCACUCUGUUCCCAAGCAGUUCAUGAUACAGCCUCACCUUUUGGCCCCAUCUCUGGUUUUUGAAAAUUUGGUCUAAGGAAUAAAUAGCUUUUACACUGGCUCACGAAAAUCUGCCCUGCUAGAAUUUGCUUUUCAAAAUGGAAAUAAAUUCCAACUCUCCUAAGAGGCAUUUAAUUAAGGCUCUACUUCCAGGUUGAGUAGGAAUCCAUUCUGAACAAACUACAAAAAUGUGACUGGGAAGGGGGCUUUGAGAGACUGGGACUGCUCUGGGUUAGGUUUUCUGUGGACUGAAAAAUCGUGUCCUUUUCUCUAAAUGAAGUGGCAUCAAGGACUCAGGGGGAAAGAAAUCAGGGGACAUGUUAUAGAAGUUAUGAAAAGACAACCACAUGGUCAGGCUCUUGUCUGUGGUCUCUAGGGCUCUGCAGCAGCAGUGGCUCUUCGAUUAGUUAAAACUCUCCUAGGCUGACACAUCUGGGUCUCAAUCCCCUUGGAAAUUCUUGGUGCAUUAAAUGAAGCCUUACCCCAUUACUGCGGUUCUUCCUGUAAGGGGGCUCCAUUUUCCUCCCUCUCUUUAAAUGACCACCUAAAGGACAGUAUAUUAACAAGCAAAGUCGAUUCAACAACAGCUUCUUCCCAGUCACUUUUUUUUUUCUCACUGCCAUCACAUACUAACCUUAUACUUUGAUCUAUUCUUUUUGGUUAUGAGAGAAAUGUUGGGCAACUGUUUUUACCUGAUGGUUUUAAGCUGAACUUGAAGGACUGGUUCCUAUUCUGAAACAGUAAAACUAUGUAUAAUAGUAUAUAGCCAUGCAUGGCAAAUAUUUUAAUAUUUCUGUUUUCAUUUCCUGUUGGAAAUAUUAUCCUGCAUAAUAGCUAUUGGAGGCUCCUCAGUGAAAGAUCCCAAAAGGAUUUUGGUGGAAAACUAGUUGUAAUCUCACAAACUCAACACUACCAUCAGGGGUUUUCUUUAUGGCAAAGCCAAAAUAGCUCCUACAAUUUCUUAUAUCCCUCGUCAUGUGGCAGUAUUUAUUUAUUUAUUUGGAAGUUUGCCUAUCCUUCUAUAUUUAUAGAUAUUUAUAAAAAUGUAACCCCUUUUUCCUUUCUUCUGUUUAAAAUAAAAAUAAAAUUUAUCUCAGCUUCUGUUAGCUUAUCCUCUUUGUAGUACUACUUAAAAGCAUGUCGGAAUAUAAGAAUAAAAAGGAUUAUGGGAGGGGAACAUUAGGGAAAUCCAGAGAAGGCAAAAUUGAAAAAAAGAUUUUAGAAUUUUAAAAUUUUCAAAGAUUUCUUCCAUUCAUAAGGAGACUCAAUGAUUUUAAUUGAUCUAGACAGAAUUAUUUAAGUUUUAUCAAUAUUGGAUUUCUGGU